ACUGCGCGCCGCCUCCGAGGCGGCCUAGGUGCGGUGGGCGCUCGUCCCCGGCUGUCCCCCGACUCCCGGCAGUCCUGUGAGUGCUGCGCCUUUAGCCCCACGGGGUGGAGAUGCAUGGGUUCCCCAGAUCGGGACCAGAGAGCCAGAGUUAAGCCUGGCCCCGAGGCCGCCGCGCGUGGGGAGGGAGGGCUGCGGGCCUAGGUCGCGAACCGCCUCUCAGCGGGGAACAGCCGCAUUGGGUUGCCAGGAAGCCCUAAGGUUCCUCCACCAACAAUCUUUGGCAGGUCAAGUCCUGACAGUGCCCUCACUUUGAUGGGGUGGGAAGGGAGGUUGGUGAUCGCUCUGCAGGGUUAAGGUAAUCCUGAAGGCUGAAAUGCGGGGCAGAAUCGAAGGUACUUUGGGGGAAAAUGAAAUUUCAUUACCUUAGGUAUCUAGGAUUGAUGUAUUCUAUCUUCUGUUUGAGAAUUUUGGUCUUCAAGCCUUCGAUUUUUAAGAAAAUAGAUAAGUGUUUUUUUUCCCUCAGUUUCUGGUGCUCUUUGGGAGAAUGGGAAACUGACAAGGCCAAUUUCAGUUUACACCGUUUCAGAUGUCAAAGGAGCGCUAGGAGGCCAUGGUACUUUACUAGAUUAACCAUAGUACUUCCCUCAAGUGAUUCAGAAGACGGGCUAGAAAAUACAGCGGAGAAUACAUAGGCUGCCAUCUACAAAACAAAUGAUUGUAAUGGCUGGUUCUUUUCUGAAAUGAAGUAAUAGUGGGGUCGGUUCACUGCUUUUCUCUUUUCCUAGUAGUUGGGUAGGCUACGAUGGUGCAACUUCGGUUCCUGAGGUUGUAUACUAUCUGUAUACUGCCAGGAAUUUAGGGUGGUGCUAAACAGAUUGCAAUGUCAGGGUACCGGCUUGCAGCUACUAAAUGUAUUUACUCCAGGAAUAACUUUUAUGUACCCAUAUUGUGAUUUGCACUUGGGAAAUCAGUCAUAAAAACUGAUGUUACCUGUGAAGGCCCAUGUUAUGGUAGACCUCCGCAAAACUAUACCUAAUUGUAGAGUAGAAACUGAAAGCUUUCUAUUCUCAAUGGUCAAGACUUUGCCUGCAGGUAGGAGAGAAUCUCAGAAAAAUAACAGGGAGCAACAUUAAUCCACUGAUCCCCAUUGCUGAUUUAUAAAGUACACCACCUUAAGUAGGCUUUUAGGCUAUUUUCAGUUUUUUAAGUCUGGCCUCAUUUUACCUUUCCAGGACUCUAUGGAAAAAUGAAUUGUUUACUGCCCUGGGGACUGUGUUCUUUCAUGGCAUGUUCACACCAUAUACCCUCCUGGAAUGCCCUGUUUCCAUCUCUAUCUAUCAAUCUCCUGUCAUAAAAUCUUCCACAAAACUUUUUCUGAUCACUUCAACUAAAGUUGCACUUUUCUUUUGAAUUCCUCCUGCACAUAAUGGCACUAAGCCUUGUAGUGAUAUUAGGAAAGUUAUUUCCCCCAUUUAGAGGCCAACAACCAUUUCAACCCUCUGACUCCUCUUUGCCUUGUCUCUGUGGCCACAACACCAUGCGUAUUGUAAGUAAUCAAUCGGUAUUCUCAGAUUAAUGAAGGUUAGAAAUUGCCCUUCUUUCUAGGCCAGUGUAUUUGUUCUCUAUUCCCAUAGGAAAUUUCCUUUGACUUCUAAUACAAAGCCAAACUGAAACCCUUUAACACUCCUGCUACAUUAUCCUGUCCCAUCUACUUAUUAUCACACAGUUUAGAAGACCAAACUGGACAAUGGACUUUGCUCACUAUGAUGACAUGAUCUCCAUUGACCUCCAUUUGUCUACCAUCAGAGGGAGAUCUCUGCCCCCUGGGGCUGAGAGACCCCAACCUUUCCCCAAGCUGAAGCUGCAGGGUAUUGAGGUACCAGCCAGAUGUCUUCCCACAAAGGAUCUGUGGUGGCACAGGGGAAUGGGGCUCCUGCCAGUAACAGGGAAGCUGACACGGUGGAACUGGCUGAACUGGGACCCCUGCUAGAAGAGAAGGGCAAACGGGUAAUCGCCAACCCACCCAAAGCUGAAGAAGAGCAAACAUGCCCAGUGCCCCAGGAAGAAGAGGAGGAGGUGCGGGUACUGACACUUCCCCUGCAAGCCCACCACGCCAUGGAGAAGAUGGAAGAGUUUGUGUACAAGGUCUGGGAGGGACGUUGGAGGGUCAUCCCAUAUGAUGUGCUCCCUGACUGGCUAAAGGACAACGACUAUCUGCUACAUGGUCAUAGACCUCCCAUGCCCUCCUUUCGGGCUUGCUUCAAGAGCAUCUUCCGCAUUCAUACAGAAACUGGCAACAUCUGGACCCAUCUGCUUGGUUUCGUGCUGUUUCUCUUUUUGGGAAUCUUGACCAUGCUCAGACCAAAUAUGUACUUCAUGGCCCCUCUACAGGAGAAGGUGGUUUUUGGGAUGUUCUUUUUGGGUGCAGUGCUCUGCCUCAGCUUCUCCUGGCUCUUUCACACCGUCUAUUGUCAUUCAGAGAAAGUCUCUCGGACUUUUUCCAAACUGGACUAUUCAGGGAUUGCUCUUCUAAUUAUGGGGAGCUUUGUCCCCUGGCUCUAUUAUUCCUUCUACUGCUCCCCACAGCCACGGCUCAUCUACCUCUCCAUCGUCUGUGUCCUGGGCAUUUCUGCCAUCAUUGUGGCGCAGUGGGACCGGUUUGCCACUCCUAAGCACCGGCAGACAAGAGCAGGCGUGUUCCUGGGACUUGGCUUGAGUGGCGUCGUGCCCACCAUGCACUUUACUAUCGCUGAGGGCUUUGUCAAGGCCACCACAGUGGGCCAGAUGGGCUGGUUCUUCCUCAUGGCUGUGAUGUACAUCACUGGAGCUGGCCUUUAUGCUGCUCGAAUUCCUGAGCGCUUCUUUCCUGGAAAAUUUGACAUAUGGUUCCAGUCUCAUCAGAUUUUCCAUGUCCUGGUGGUGGCAGCAGCCUUUGUCCACUUCUAUGGAGUCUCCAACCUUCAGGAAUUCCGUUACGGCCUAGAAGGCGGCUGUACUGAUGACACCCUUCUCUGAGCCUUCCCACCUGCGGGGUGGAGGAGGAACUUCCCAAGUGCUUUUAAAAAUAACUUCUUUGCUGAAGUGAGAGGAAGAGUCUGAGUUGUCUGUUUCUAGAAGAAACCUCUUAGAGAAUUCAGUACCAACCAAGCUUCAGCCCACUUUCACACCCACUGGGCAAUAAACUUUCCAUUUCCAUUCUCCUAGCUGGGGAUGGGGCAUGGUCAAACUUAGCCAUCCCCUCCUCAGCAAGGCAUCUACCGGCCCCUCACAGAGACAGUACUUUGAAACUCAUGUUGAGAUUUUACCCUCUCCUCCAACCAUUUUGGGAAAAUUAUGGACUGGGACUCUUCAGAAAUUCUGUCUUUUCUUCUGGAAGAAAAUGUCCCUCCCUUACCCCCAUCCUUAACUUUGUAUCCUGGCUUAUAACAGGCCAUCCAUUUUUGUAGCACACUUUUCAAAAACAAUUAUAUACCCUGGUCCCAUCUUUCUAGGGCCUGGAUCUGCUUAUAGAGCAGGAAGAAUAAAGCCACCAACUUUUACCUAGCCCGGCUAAUCAUGGAAGUGUGUCCAGGCUUCAAGUAACUUGAGUUUUAAUUUUUUUUUUUUCUUGGCAGAGUAAUGUAAAAUUUAAAUGGGGAAAGAUAUUUAAUAUUUAAUACUAAGCUUUAAAAAGAAACCUGCUAUCAUUGCUAUGUAUCUUGAUGCAAAGACUAUGAUGUUAAUAAAAGAAAGUACAGAAGACACUUGGCAUUCAAAGAUUUCA